AGCCAAACUUCCGGCGGCGGCUGAGGCGGCGGCCGAGGAGCGGCGGACUCGGGGCGCGGGGAGUCGAGGCAUUUGCACCUGGGCUUCGGAGCGUAGCGCCAGGGCCUGAGCCUUUGAAGCAGGAGGAGGGGAGGAGAGAGUGGGGCUCCUCUAUCGGGACCCCCUCCCCAUGUGGAUCUGCCCAGGCGGCGGCGGCGGCGGCGGCGGAGGAGGAGGAGGAGGCGACCGAGAAGAUGCCCGCCCUGCGUCCCGCUCUGCUGUGGGCGCUGCUGGCGCUCUGGCUGUGCUGGGCGGCCCCCGCGCAUGCAUUGCAGUGUCGAGAUGGCUAUGAACCCUGUGUAAAUAAAGGAAUGUGUGUUACCUACCACAGUGGCACAGGAUACUGCAAAUGUCCAGAAGGCUUCUUGGGGGAAUAUUGUCAACAUCGAGACCCCUGUGAGAAGAACCGCUGCCAGAAUGGUGGGACUUGUGUGGCCCAGGCCAUGCUGGGGAAAGCCACGUGCCGGUGUGCCUCAGGGUUUACAGGAGAGGACUGCCAGUACUCGACACCUCAUCCAUGCUUUGUGUCUCGACCUUGCCUGAAUGGCGGCACAUGCCAUAUGCUCAGCCGGGAUACCUAUGAGUGCACCUGUCAAGUCGGGUUUACAGGUAAGGAGUGCCAAUGGACCGAUGCCUGCCUGUCUCAUCUCUGUGCAAAUGGAAGUACCUGUACCACUGUGGCCAACCAGUUCUCCUGCAAAUGCCUCACAGGCUUCACAGGGCAGAAGUGUGAGACUGAUGUCAAUGAGUGUGACAUUCCAGGACACUGCCAGCAUGGUGGCACCUGCCUCAACCUGCCUGGUUCCUACCAGUGCCAGUGCCUUCAGGGCUUCACAGGCCAGUACUGUGACAGACUGUAUGUGCCCUGUGCACACUCGCCUUGUGUCAAUGGAGGCACCUGUCGGCAGACUGGUGACUUCACUUUUGAGUGCAACUGCCUUCCAGUCCCUGACUCCACCUCUUCUGCCACAAACGUCAGCAUGGUGGUAUCAGCCGGCCAUUGGUCCAGUGAGAAGGCAGAGAUGAACAUUCUAGAAAUCAACGAGACAUUGCGCCCCCAGCUGCCAGAGAACAAACAGCAGUUGAGAAACCUCAAAGAGAAAUGUUUUCUAACUCAACUGGCCGGCUUCCUGGCCAACCGACAGAAGAAAUACAAGUAUGAAGAGUGUAAAGACCUCAUAAAAUUUAUGCUGAGGAAUGAGCGACAGUUCAAGGAGGAGAAGCUUGCAGAGCAGCUCAAGCAAGCUGAGGAGCUCAGGCAAUAUAAAGUCCUGGUUCACUCUCAGGAACGAGAGCUGACGCAGUUAAAGGAGAAGUUACGGGAAGGGAGAGAUGCCUCCCGCUCAUUGAAUGAGCAUCUCCAGGCCCUCCUCACUCCGGAUGAGCCGGACAAGUCCCAGGGGCAGGACCUCCAAGAACAGCUGGCUGAGGGGUGUAGACUGGCACAGCACCUUGUCCAAAAGCUCAGCCCAGAAAAUGACGAAGAUGAGGAUGAAGAUGUUCAAGUUGAGGAGGAUGAGAAAGUACUGGAAUCAUCUGCCCCCAGGGAGGUGCAGAAGACUGAAGAGAGCAAAGUCCCUGAGGACUCACUGGAGGAAUGUGCCAUCACUUGUUCAAAUAGCCACGGCCCUUGUGACUCCAACCAGCCUCACAAGAACAUCAAAAUCACAUUUGAGGAAGACGAAGUCAACUCAACUCUGGUUGUAGACAGAGAAUCCUCUCAUGAUGAAUGUCAGGAUGCUCUAAACAUUCUCCCAGUCCCUGGCCCCACCUCUUCUGCCACAAACGUCAGCAUGGUGGUAUCAGCCGGCCCUUUGUCCGGCGAGAAGGCAGCGAUAAACAUUCUAGAAAUCAAUGAGAAAUUGCGCCCCCAGCUGGCAGAGAAGAAACAGCAGUUCAGAAACCUCAAAGAGAAAUGUUUUCUAACUCAACUGGCCGGCUUCCUGGCCAACCAGCAGAACAAAUACAAAUAUGAAGAGUGCAAAGAUCUCAUAAAAUCUAUGCUGAGGAAUGAGCGACAGUUCAAGGAGGAGAAGCUUGCAGAGCAGCUCAAGCAAGCUGAGGAGCUCAGGCAAUAUAAAGUCCUGGUUCACGCUCAGGAACGAGAGCUGACCCAGUUAAGGGAGAAGUUGCGGGAAGGGAGAGAUGCCUCCCGCUCAUUGAAUGAGCAUCUCCAGGCCCUCCUCACUCCGGAUGAGCCGGACAAGUCCCAGGGGCAGGACCUCCAAGAACAGCUGGCUGAGGGGUGUAGACUGGCACAGCACCUUGUCCAAAAGCUCAGCCCAGAAAAUGACAACGAUGACGAUGAAGAUGUUCAAGUUGAGGUGGCUGAGAAAGUGCAGAAAUCGUCUGCCCCCAGGGAGAUGCAGAAGGCUGAAGAAAAGGAAGUCCCUGAGGACUCACUGGAGGAAUGUGCCAUCACUUGUUCAAAUAGCCAUGGCCCUUAUGACUGCAACCAGCCACAUAGGAAAACCAAAAUCACAUUUGAGGAAGACAAAGUCGACUCAACUCUCAUUGGCUCAUCCUCUCAUGUUGAAUGGGAGGAUGCUGUACACAUUAUUCCAGAAAAUGAAAGUGAUGAUGAGGAAGAGGAAGAAAAAGGACCAGUGUCUCCCAGGAAUCUGCAGGAGUCUGAAGAGGAGGAAGUCCCCCAGGAGUCCUGGGAUGAAGGUUAUUCGACUCUCUCAAUUCCUCCUGAAAUGUUAGCCUCGUACAAGUCUUACAGCAGCACAUUUCACUCAUUAGAGGAACAGCAAGUCUGCAUGGCUGUUGACAUAGGCAGACAUCGGUGGGAUCAAGUGAAAAAGGAGGACCACGAGGCAACAGGUCCCAGGCUCAGCAGAGAGCUGCUGGAUGAGAAAGGGCCUGAAGUCUUGCAGGACUCACUGGAUAGAUGUUAUUCAACUCCUUCAGGUUGUCUUGAACUGACUGACUCAUGCCAGCCCUACAGAAGUGCCUUUUACGUAUUGGAGCAACAGCGUGUUGGCUUGGCUGUUGACAUGGAUGAAAUUGAAAAGUACCAAGAAGUGGAAGAAGACCAAGACCCAUCAUGCCCCAGGCUCAGCGGGGAGCUGUUGGAUGAGAAAGAGCCUGAAGUCUUGCAGGAGUCACUGGAUAGAUGCUAUUCAACUCCUUCAGGUUGUCUUGAACUGACUGACUCAUGCCAGCCCUACAGAAGUGCCUUUUACAUAUUGGAGCAACAGCGUGUUGGCUUGGCUGUUGACAUGGAUGAAAUUGAAAAGUACCAAGAAGUGGAAGAAGACCAAGACCCAUCAUGCCCCAGGCUCAGCGGGGAGCUGUUGGAUGAGAAAGAGCCUGAAGUCUUGCAGGAGUCACUGGAUAGAUGCUAUUCAACUCCUUCAGGUUGUCUUGAACUGACUGACUCAUGCCAGCCCUACAGAAGUGCCUUUUACAUAUUGGAGCAACAGCGUGUUGGCUUGGCUGUUGACAUGGAUGAAAUUGAAAAGUACCAAGAAGUGGAAGAAGACCAAGACCCAUCAUGCCCCAGGCUCAGCAGGGAGCUGCUGGAUGAGAAAGAGCCUGAAGUCUUGCAGGACUCACUGGGUAGAUGUUAUUCGACUCCUUCAGGUUAUCUUGAACUGCCUGACUUAGGCCAGCCCUACAGCAGUGCUGUUUACUCAUUGGAGGAACAGUACCUUGGCUUGGCUCUUGACGUGGACAGAAUUAAAAAGGACCAAGAAGAGGAAGAAGACCAAGGCCCACCAUGCCCCAGGCUCAGCAGGGAGCUGCUGGAGGUAGUAGAGCCUGAAGUCUUGCAGGACUCACUGGAUAGAUGUUAUUCAACUCCUUCCAGUUGUCUUGAACAGCCUGACUCCUGCCAGCCCUAUGGAAGUUCCUUUUAUGCAUUGGAGGAAAAACAUGUUGGCUUUUCUCUUGACGUGGGAGAAAUUGAAAAGAAGGGGAAGGGGAAGAAAAGAAGGGGAAGAAGAUCAAAGAAGGAAAGAAGAAGGGGAAGAAAAGAAGGGGAAGAAGAUCAAAACCCACCAUGCCCCAGGCUCAGCAGGGAGCUGCUGGAUGAGAAAGGGCCUGAAGUCUUGCAGGACUCACUGGAUAGAUGUUAUUCAACUCCUUCAGGUUGUCUUGAACUGACUGACUCAUGCCAGCCCUACAGAAGUGCCUUUUACAUAUUGGAGCAACAGCGUGUUGGCUUGGCUGUUGACAUGGAUGAAAUUGAAAAGUACCAAGAAGUGGAAGAAGACCAAGACCCAUCAUGCCCCAGGCUCAGCAGGGAGCUGCUGGAGGUAGUAGAGCCUGAAGUCUUGCAGGACUCACUGGAUAGAUGUUAUUCAACUCCUUCCAGUUGUCUUGAACAGCCUGACUCCUGCCAGCCCUAUGGAAGUUCCUUUUAUGCAUUGGAGGAAAAACAUGUUGGCUUUUCUCUUGACGUGGGAGAAAUUGAAAAGUACCAAGAAGUGGAAGAAGACCAAGACCCAUCAUGCCCCAGGCUCAGCAGGGAGCUGCUGGAUGAGAAAGAGCCUGAAGUCUUGCAGGACUCACUGGGUAGAUGUUAUUCGACUCCUUCAGGUUAUCUUGAACUGCCUGACUUAGGCCAGCCCUACAGCAGUGCUGUUUACUCAUUGGAGGAACAGUACCUUGGCUUGGCUCUUGACGUGGACAGAAUUAAAAAGGACCAAGAAGAGGAAGAAGACCAAGGCCCACCAUGCCCCAGGCUCAGCAGGGAGCUGCUGGAGGUAGUAGAGCCUGAAGUCUUGCAGGACUCACUGGAUAGAUGUUAUUCAACUCCUUCCAGUUGUCUUGAACAGCCUGACUCCUGCCAGCCCUAUGGAAGUUCCUUUUAUGCAUUGGAGGAAAAACAUGUUGGCUUUUCUCUUGACGUGGGAGAAAUUGAAAAGAAGGGGAAGGGGAAGAAAAGAAGGGGAAGAAGAUCAAAGAAGGAAAGAAGAAGGGGAAGAAAAGAAGGGGAAGAAGAUCAAAACCCACCAUGCCCCAGGCUCAACAGCAUGCUGAUGGAAGUGGAAGAGCCUGAAGUCUUGCAGGACUCACUGGAUAUAUGUUAUUCGACUCCGUCAAUGUACUUUGAACUACCUGACUCAUUCCAGCACUACAGAAGUGUGUUUUACUCAUUUGAGGAAGAGCAUAUCAGCUUCGCCCUUUACGUGGACAAUAGGUUUUUUACUUUGACGGUGACAAGUCUCCACCUGGUGUUCCAGAUGGGAGUCAUAUUCCCACAAUAAGCAGCCCUUACUAAGCCGAGAGGUGUCAUUCCUGCAGGCAGGACCUAUAGGCACGUGAAGAUUUGAAUGAAAGUACAGUUCCAUUUGGAAGCCCAGACAUAGGAUGGUUCAGUGGGCAUGGCUCUAUUCCUAUUCUCAAACCAUGCCAGUGGCAACCUGUGCUCAGUCUGAAGACAAUGGACCCACGUUAGGUGUGACACGUUCACAUAACUGUGCAGCACAUGCCGGGAGUGAUCAGUCAGACAUUUUAAUUUGAACCACGUAUCUCUGGGUAGCUACAAAAUUCCUCAGGGAUGUCAUUUUGCAGGCAUGUCUCUGAGCUUCUAUACCUGCUCAAGGUCAUUGUCAUCUUUGUGUUUAGCUCAUCCAAAGGUGUUACCCUGGUUUCAAUGAACCUAACCUCAUUCUUUGUGUCUUCAGUGUUGGCUUGUUUUAGCUGAUCCAUCUGUAACACAGGAGGGAUCCUUGGCUGAGGAUUGUAUUUCAGAACCACCAACUGCUCUUGACAAUUGUUAACCCGCUAGGCUCCUUUGGUUAGAGAAGCCACAGUCCUUCAGCCUCCAAUUGGUGUCAGUACUUAGGAAGACCACAGCUAGAUGGACAAACAGCAUUGGGAGGCCUUAGCCCUGCUCCUCUCAAUUCCAUCCUGUAGAGAACAGGAGUCAGGAGCCGCUGGCAGGAGACAGCAUGUCACCCAGGACUCUGCCGGUGCAGAAUAUGAGCAAUGCCAUGUUCUUGCAGAAAACGCUUAACCUGAGUUUCAUAGGAGGUAAUCACCAGACAACUGCAGAAUGUAGAACACUGAGCAGGACAACUGACCUGUCUCCUUCACAUAGUCCAUAUCACCACAAAUCACACAACAAAAAGGAGAAGAGAUAUUUUCGGUUGAAAAAAAGUAAAAAGAUAAUGUAGCUGCAUUUCUUUAGUUAUUUUGAACCCCAAAUAUUUCCUCAUCUUUUUGUUGUUGUCAUGGAUGGUGGUGACAUGGACUUGUUUAUAGAGGACAGGUCAGCUGUCUGGCUCAAUGAUCUACAUUCUGAAGUUGUCUGAAAAUGUCUUCAUGAUUAAAUUCAGCCUAAACGUUUUGCCGGGAACACUGCAGAGACAAUGCUGUGAGUUUCCAACCUCAGCCCAUCUGCGGGCAGAGAAGGUCUAGUUUGUCCAUCACCAUUAUGAUAUCAGGACUGGUUACUUGGUUAAGGAGGGGUCUAGGAGAUCUGUCCCUUUUAGAGACACCUUACUUAUAAUGAAGUACUUGGGAAAGCAGUUUUCAAGAGUAUAAAUAUCCUGUAUUCUAAUGAUCAUCCUCUAAACAUUUUAUCAUUUAUUAAUCCUCCCUGCCUGUGUCUAUUAUUAUAUUCAUAUCUCUACACUGCAAAUUUUGGGUCUCAAUUUUUACUGUGCCUUUGUUUUUACUAGUGUCUGCUGUUGCAAAAAGAAGAAAACAUUCUCUGCCUGAGUUUUAAUUUUUGUCCAAAGUUAAUUUUAAUCUAUACAAUUAAAACCUUUUGCUAUCACUCUGGACUUUUGGAUUGUUUUUUACAUUCAGUGUUAUAAUAUUUGAUUAUGCUGAUUGGUUUUGGUGGGUACUGAUGCGAAUUAAUAAAAACAUUUCAUUUCCAUGUUUAUUUUCUAA